CUUGCCCCUCCGGCGCUUGGGCCAGAGUGGUGCGGGCGGCGCGUGGCGGCGAUCCCCACGUGGUGGCUUUCUCACGCUAGCCCUCUUUGGUCCUCCUUGACGUCCCGGGCCUGUGGGCCCGCUUUCUGCCGAGAUGCCGAAGGUCAAGUCGGGGGCCAUCGGCCGCCGCCGCGGGCGGCAGGAGCAGCGCCGGGAGCUGAAGAGCGCUGGAGGACUCAUGUUCAACACGGGGAUUGGGCAGCACAUUUUGAAAAAUCCUCUCAUUAUUAACAGCAUUAUCGAUAAGGCUGCCUUAAGACCAACUGAUGUAGUGCUGGAAGUUGGACCUGGAACUGGCAACAUGACUGUAAAGUUGUUAGAAAAGGCAAAAAAGGUUGUUGCUUGUGAACUUGACCCAAGGCUAGUAGCUGAACUUCACAAAAGAGUUCAGGGCACGCCUGUGGCCAGCAAACUUCAAGUACUGGUGGGUGAUGUGCUGAAAACAGAUUUGCCAUUCUUUGAUACUUGUGUGGCAAAUUUGCCUUAUCAGAUCUCUUCACCUUUUGUCUUCAAGCUGUUGCUACAUCGACCUUUUUUCAGGUUUGUGACAAAAGACUAGAGUUACUGCCAAAUUUUGAAAGACUUACAGUUCAGGUGGUGAACAUAGCCAAAAAUGAGUCAGGUGUGCUAUACUUAUGUUUCAAAGAGAAUUUGCCCUCCGACUGGUUGCAAAACCUGGAGAUAAGUUAUACUGCAGACUCUCAAUUAAUACACAGCUGUUGGCACGUGUGGACCAUCUAAUGAAAGUGGGAAAGAAUAACUUCAGACCACCGCCCAAGGUGGAAUCCAGUGUUGUAAGGAUAGAACCUAAGAAUCCACCACCACCCAUCAAUUUUCAGGAAUGGGAUGGUCUAGUAAGGAUAACCUUUGUUAGGAAAAACAAGACACUCUCUGCUGCAUUUAAAUCAAGUGCAGUGCAACAACUCUUGGAAAAAAACUACAGAAUUCACUGUUCAGUCCAUAAUAUUAUAAUACCAGAAGAUUUCAGCAUAGCAGAUAAAAUACAGCAAAUCCUAACCAGCACAGGUUUUAGUGACAAACGGGCCCGUUCCAUGGACAUAGAUGACUUCAUCAGAUUGCUACAUGGAUUCAACGCAGAAGGUAUUCAUUUUUCCUAGGUAUUUGGAAAACAGAAAUUUUCAAGGUCAAGAAAAGAAAUGAAUUUUGUAUUUUUUGUAUUUGAGAAGAUAAUGCUUUUGCUUUACUGAGACAUUAUUUACUUGACUAUUUUUGGUUCAAUACUACUACUGUUGUCACCAUUUAUGAUUCUGAAUUUUAAAGUUGGAAAGUUCUAAGUAUCAAAGUUUUUAAUAUAUAAUGCUGGUCCAAUCUAUUCAUAAUAAUCUUCAAGUUCAGGAGCCGCAGAGACGCACAACUUUACACUUAUCAUUUCUAACAGUUUAUUGUAUAAAGAUGUUACUCUUCUAUUUACUGUUAUAUACUGUAAGGCCUUCUUUAGGCCUUUAGCUCUGUUCCUCCAGUAAUAAAAAAGUUAAAAUAUGCUUCACUAGUCACACAUUCCCCAUACCAUUUCGUGUUAUUCACAUUCCCCGUACCAUUUCUUGUUAUUCACAUGUACAGUAAAACAAUUGUUUCUUAAAUUAUUUUUAUUUUGGUUCUCUCAUUCUCUUCCCUAUUUAUCCUAUACAGUGUCUGUUACGAUUGCCUACCUCUUUCGCUAUCCUAUAGCGUCAGAGACUUAGGGUUCUGGGUAAGCCCAAGUCUGCUACUGCCACCGUGCAGUGCCAGGCAUAUUAAAGGGCAUGACUCCCAACAUGUAAAAUGAGGAAGCUAAACUGGAAUGAAAUUAACAAUAAAAUUAUCUUUUUUUAUGGUUCUUAGGGAGAUAACUAUAGGCUUAGCAAAAUUUCAGAGGGUUUUGUAAUUGAAACUGGUUUCAACUUCAGAAAAACAGCCAUUUCCCAUAACUACAGGUUCCCAGUAUUCCUAUGAUUUCUGGACAAUUAAAAUUUCCAGUUCCUUUUUCAUAUACCUGGUGCUUAGUUUUAAGCUAUUUUAAAACUGUCAGACUGAGAAUUUCAAUAGAUGUCAUAAACUAGUUUUAUUAGCUACUAUGUUUAAGUCAAUAUAAUACUAAGUGCUGUUAAUAUACUAUAAUAGAGUUAUAGUAGCUAUUUUGUUUCUAUAAAAAAUUAAUAAAAAUAUCUUUAUUGAUAUUUGGCUUUUUUUAAUACCUAACUUAAUAGAAGAGUGUUUCCAAUUAAUUUAACAAAGCCAGAUUUUGAAAUCUGGCUUCAAAGUCAUAGUAAAUGUUACUACAUAAUUAAAAUAAUGCUUGUUCUUAAUGUAUAAUCCAGAACAAAGGCAUCAAGCUGCUUUUGUUAAACAAAUAUGAAAUAAUAUACAUUAAGAGUAGAUUUUUUUGUUUAAUUUCACAAAACUAUUUUGCAGAGUUCACUUGUAUCAUCUCUAUCCUUAUAGUAAAAAUUUUAAGAUUUAACUCGGCUUUCUCAGGUUAUUUCCCUCUACCCCUAUGAACUGCUGAGUUUUAGUUCCUUUUCUGGCCUUCAGUUUUCACUAUCUGUAAAGCUGAAGGACUGUAUUAUAUUACCUCCAGUAUCUUUUCUGGUACUAAUUUUUAAAAUACCUGAUCAGAAUGAAGCCAUCAUAGUGUAAGGCAGCAUAUUUGUCUAUAAGGAGACUUUCCAAAGACAGUACCCAUCCAAUGCAAAUAAUAAAUUUGAAGCUAAUCAUCUGUUGUGCUUUAAAAUGAGCAAAUUCACAUGUCUUUAUUGCCCUUUGAAAGUUGGUUAAUCUCAAAAACUACCUUUUUUUUAAAUAUCCUUUGCAAGGUCAAUUGUAACAGUUCUCCAUCCUUCCUCUUCCCUUUGAAAUAAACACAAAUAGAAUAUA